ACACGCCCGAGGCGCGCUGGAUUGGCGGUGAGUUCUGACUCCGGCCUCCUUCGAGACCGUUUCGCUCCGGAUGUCGCCCACCUCCGACCCUCUCUCAGUCGGAGGGCGGAAAAGAGGAAGAUAGGUCCUUCCUCCAGCCGCGGGGCACCCCCUUCUCCCACCUUGCCCUUCCCCCAGCCCUGCAGCCCCAGAGUGAGCAUGGCCCAGGAGGAGGGUGGGAGCCUGCCCGAGGUGCGGGCGCGGGUCAGGGCCGCGCAUGGCAUCCCCGACCUGGCCCAAAAGCUCCAUUUCUAUGACCGCUGGGCUCCGGACUACGACCAGGAUGUGGCCACCCUGCUGUACCGUGCGCCCCGCCUCGCAGUGGACUGCCUCACACAAGCCCUUCCAGGCCCGCCCCACAGUGCCCUGAUCCUGGACGUGGCCUGUGGCACAGGCCUAGUGGCUGCCGAGCUGCGGGCUCCAGGCUUCCUCCAGCUGCAUGGGGUGGAUGGGAGCCCAGGGAUGCUGGAACAGGCCCAGGCCCCCGGCCUCUAUCAGCGCCUCAGCCUCUGCACCCUGGGCCAGGAGCCUCUGCCCAGCCCGGAAGGGACCUUCGACGCGGUGCUGAUAGUCGGUGCCCUCAGUGACGGCCAGGUGCCCUGCAAUGCGAUACCUGAGCUACAUGUCACCAAGCCAGGGACAACCAUCCCCAGCAGAGAUGGCCCAGGACUGUGGCUCCUGCCCCUCCCCCACCUCACCUACCCCUCUCCCCCAGGUGGGCUGGUGUGUCUGACCACCAGGACCAACUCGUCCAACCUUCAAUACAAGGAGGCUCUGGAGGCCACCCUGGACAGGCUGGAGCAGGCUGGGAUGUGGGAAGGCCUGGUGGCCUGGCCUGUGGACCGCCUGUGGACCGCUGGGAGCUGGCUACCUCCGAGCUGGAGGUGGUAUCCGGCAUCUCUGCCAAGGAUGGCUUCAUCUCCGGCAUUGUCUACCUGUACCGAAAGUGGAAGGCGACCCAGGUUGAGGAAGUGAGAUCCAGCCCCCAGCCCCCAGCUGGCCCCUGACUCCAUGUGGCCUUAGCUGGGCCCAUCUGCUGGGCCUCCUCUGCCUCCCCUGUAAAAUGGGACCUCCGAACCAACCCUGCCCCUCAGAAAUGCCCUGCCUAUUAAAUGAGCUCCCAGAAAA